AGGGGCCCGCCGCGCCCAUCCCGAUGGCUGGAGGCGUCUGAGGGGCGGACGGAGGCGGCGGCGGCGGCGGCGGGAGCGGGAGCGGGCGGCGAGUGGGGAGCGGGGCCGGGAGUGGAGCAGCCGCCGCGGCGGGACUGGACCGAGCCUCGCCGGCGCGCACCUGCCCGCAGCGCCCGCGGAGCGCGCAGCGCGGCCCGAGCGCGACGACCUGCCGAGCGGCGGCCGAGGCGGCGGUGUGGGCGCGUCAGGCCGCGACGAGGGCGCUGAGCUGCAUAUCUAUGUGAGACUGAAUUUUCCUCUUAGACUUCAGCUAAAACUGUGUAUUGCAUCAGGCUGAGAGCAGACACGAUGUGAAGAUCCAUUGCUCCCAUUGAGGCAGACAAGGAGGAGUAUUUGAAGACUUCUGAGCGGAGGAGUCGCAUGUCAGAGCUGUCCUUCAGAAAGAUAAAUCAGGCAGUGCUGUUAAGAUGGAUUGAAGUGGAAAAGAGGUGGGAUAGAGACACAGAUUAGUAACGGGCCAGGCAAAGAUGGUUGAGGCUGAGGAGGAGAAAGAGAUGGGAUUGGUCUUGCUGUCUUGGAUGGAGGUGGUGGAAGGGGAGGUAGGAGAGACAGGCAUACUUGGUGGAACUUUACUGAAAUACAUAAUUUCUGACUUCUUUCUUUUUCGUUUUAUUUUUUCUUUUUCUUUUUUUUUUUUUUUUUGCCUGGGCUGGAGUGCAAUGGCUCAGUCUUGGCUCACUGCAGCCUCCGCCUCCUGGGUUCAAGCGGUUUUCCUGCUUCAGCCUCCCAAGUAGCUGGGAUUACAGGCGCCCGCCACCAUGCCCGGCUAAUUUUUUUUAUUUUUAGUAGAGACAGAGUUUCACUGUGUUGGCCAGGGUGGUCUGGAACACCUGAUCUCGUGGUCUGCCCGCUUUGGCCUCCCAAAGUGCUGGGAGUACAGGCCUGAGCCACCGCACCCGGCCUGCUUUUUCAUUUCUCUAAAAAAGUUUCUGUAUGAUAGCAACCUUCUGUUGUAUGCUUUAGUUUUAGUUCCUGUGCCAUAAAAGCUCUGUGUCCUAAAGAAGUCAAGUGCAGUCUUGGGGAAUGGGGACCUUCUGCCAGAUUGCCCAGUGUCCACGUGUUUUUGGCACUGCUUCUUUCUCAUCGUUUGGCACCACGUUGGAAGUACUGACAUCUGUCAAGACAAAUUUACAUGUAUUGGAGACCAGACCAGAAGCCCUUCUGAAUUAAGAUCUCACAUUCUUGAAGGUGGCAUUGAAGAGCACUAAGAUCGGAAGAUGAGUGAGCUUGACCAGUUACGGCAGGAGGCCGAGCAACUUAAGAACCAGAUUCGAGACGCCAGGAAAGCAUGUGCAGAUGCAACUCUCUCUCAGAUCACAAACAACAUCGACCCAGUGGGAAGAAUCCAAAUGCGCACGAGGAGGACACUGCGGGGGCACCUGGCCAAGAUCUACGCCAUGCACUGGGGCACAGACUCCAGGCUUCUCGUCAGUGCCUCGCAGGAUGGUAAACUUAUCAUCUGGGACAGCUACACCACCAACAAGGUCCACGCCAUCCCUCUGCGCUCCUCCUGGGUCAUGACCUGUGCAUAUGCCCCUUCUGGGAACUAUGUGGCCUGCGGUGGCCUGGAUAACAUUUGCUCCAUUUACAAUCUGAAAACUCGUGAGGGGAACGUGCGCGUGAGUCGUGAGCUGGCAGGACACACAGGUUACCUGUCCUGCUGCCGAUUCCUGGAUGACAAUCAGAUCGUCACCAGCUCUGGAGACACCACGUGUGCCCUGUGGGACAUCGAGACCGGCCAGCAGACGACCACGUUUACCGGACACACUGGAGAUGUCAUGAGCCUUUCUCUUGCUCCUGACACCAGACUGUUCGUCUCUGGUGCUUGUGAUGCUUCAGCCAAACUCUGGGAUGUGCGAGAAGGCAUGUGCCGGCAGACCUUCACUGGCCACGAGUCUGACAUCAAUGCCAUUUGCUUCUUUCCAAAUGGCAAUGCAUUUGCCACUGGCUCAGACGACGCCACCUGCAGGCUGUUUGACCUUCGUGCUGACCAGGAGCUCAUGACUUACUCCCAUGACAACAUCAUCUGCGGGAUCACCUCUGUCUCCUUCUCCAAGAGCGGGCGCCUCCUCCUUGCUGGGUACGACGACUUCAACUGCAACGUCUGGGAUGCACUCAAAGCCGACCGGGCAGGUGUCUUGGCUGGGCAUGACAACCGCGUCAGCUGCCUGGGCGUGACUGACGAUGGCAUGGCUGUGGCGACAGGGUCCUGGGAUAGCUUCCUCAAGAUCUGGAACUAACGCCAGUAGCAUGUGGAUGCCAUGGAGACUGGAAGACCAUUCCAACUUGGACGCGUUACCAUGAGAGCAUAUCCUAUCCAACCGUACUAACGUGGACACCCUACACCUCCCCUCAGAACUUCAAAAGGGCAAGAUCUUUUUUCCUUCACUUAUUGCUGAAACCAAGAGCACAAUUCCCAUUGAGAGAAAGAUCUCUGUGCUGUAAACUAAAACAAAUUGUGCAUUCCUUCCGGGGCCAUCGUCUUUGUUUUCUUUUUUGUCUUGAAUGAAUUUUAAAAGGAAAUAUAUAAUAAAAAUGUUAACCAGAAGGUAAACUUGAGUGUAAUUGUCAGACAGACACACUUUUCCACCAGUGUAUUUGAAUUUUAGACCAGUGACCCUGUUUUGUGGCAUUCAUGCAAAACAUGCUGAGGGCUUUGUUCAUCUGGUCAUCGUGUCCAAAUUUCAGUCAUGUUUGUAGCAAGAUUUUGGAAGCAUUCAUAUUUCCUUUUUAAAAUGUAUUCCUUUGUGUUCAACAGUUAAUCAAAACCAGAGAGUCUAGGGCAGCCUCUCUGAUGUUGUCAAUGAUGUAAAUUCAGUCCCUGGUUUUUAAUUUUCUGUCUGAUGUCACAGAUCAUUGUUGCACACAAACGUGGCAUAGAAAAGAACAUGUUCAGAAGCCAUGGGGCCAAGCACAUGCGGGGACGGUCUCAAAUGCGUGAUCAGAGAAUCCUUCACCUUUGCUGAAAAGUGAGCUCAGAUCCAGCACCAUGUUCCUCCUGACCCAUCCUGUCUAUCUUCUCAGUUGAGUUUUUAAUCUCACUUUGGGUUUCCUUGUGAAGUUGGAGGGAAGUUUAUAAUAGCCUAACACUACCCCACCCCCAACUAGGAGGAACCUCUGUUUUCAAGAGAGAUGCCUGUCCUGUGCUUGGAUAGUCAGUCAAUUAUUUGUGUAUGAAACAAUGUACAAAUCAAUGUUUUGAAAAUAAUGAUCUCAGACUUUCUAAGUUAAAUUUUAAAAAUUUUGAUUGUUUGCCAUAUUGGGUGGGUUUACUCUUAGAAUCGCAUGCUGUAGAAAUGCUCAAAAGUGCAUAUGGGACUCAGUCCUUAGGUGUUCUUUUUCUUUUAAGAAAUAACCUCUUACAGUUGUAACCAUUGCGGCUCUGUCCACUUCUCGUUGCUGCUCUGUGGCACAUAUCGGAAGCAGUACAGCGCGCGGCUCUACACGCUUGGGUAGCGGGAUAAGUCACUGUUUUCUUUAUUUCUUUAAAAAAAAAAAAGUUCUGUUGCAAACGACUGCUGUUGGAUUCUGAGGGUGGGGAGGGAGAGAGAGGGAGGGAGAGGGAGUGAAGAGCCUGCCCUCCUAUAUGGAUUCUUCAGGGCCCUCCACAUCUGAGGUGGCUCAUUCCCAUCACACACAGAUUGUCCUGGUGUUCAUUUCAAGGCCAGUGUUCAGCAGCAGCGUUUGGAAAGCAGGUUCUGUGGGACCCCCCGCCCCGCCCCCCGCACUCCUUCAUAGCAGCAGUAGUGGCUUCUCCAUCCUGUUUUCUGCAACAUUCUAUACAAAACUGUGCUGUGACCUUGCGGUAGGCCUGGAUCUGGCAAAGAGAAUACAAAUGAAACCCCUUCUUUCUCUUUCCGUCCAACAACUCUGUAGAGCUCUCUGCACCCUUACCCCUUUCCACCUUUUGUAUUUAAUUUUAAAGUCAGUGUACUGCAAGGAAGCUGGAUGCAAGAUAGAUACUAUAUUAAACUGUACUGUUAUUUAAGAUGUAAUAAAGCAGUUUGACAUGAGGGA